AGAAAGCAGGCGAGCCUGGGCCGGCGCGGGGCCUUGUGGGAGGGCUUAAGGAAGUAAAAUGGCGGACCUGGCGAACGAAGGUAGGGGAGGCGCCGUUGGGGACCGGCUGGCGGCCGGGGAACGGGCGGCGGGAGGACUAGGGGCCACAAGCCCUUGGGGGGAGCACCGCAGAGUGCAAGGGUUUCGUCCGCUCCAGGCUAGCGCCGUGGCGGGCCUUGCAGCCGCCCCCUAUUGCGUCCCCUCAGGCCGGGCUCACCGGCCCGGCCCAUCACUCCCGGCAACCCCAGCCACUGCAGCCGUCUGGCUAGAGGAGCCGGGUGGCCAUCGGGAUCGCAGCCCUAAGGCCCCUCUGCGUCGCAGCCAAGCUCGGGGCUGAAGGGGGCGGGAGGCGCGGCCCCAGUGCUUCGGCCACGGAUGUAAAUAGACCUUAGGGCCUGGUUGUGGCCCGGAGCGCGCCACGCUCCCUCCCCGCCCCCUCGUCCUCCGCCACCCGGCAUCUCCCCUUCCCCGGCCUGGCUGCCUAUCUCCUAAGCCCGUGAGGCCCUCGUCCUCCGCGGGCCAGCCGCACACCGCGGACGGAGGAAGCCCAGGCCGUUUUCACCCCGUCCCCGCCCCGAACUUCGGCCCCCACUUCCCGCCAGUUCCCCCCGGAUCCUUCGGGGCGCUUCGUCUCCCCCUCAUUUAGGCCCCGCCGCAGGAUCUGGGCCGCCGAAAACCCUGGCUGCUCUUUGGCCCUUUUUGCUGCACUUCCAGACAAGAGACCGUGCGAGUCCCUCCUCUGUGGAGCGCUGACAGCCCACCUGAGUGUUUUUGACAAGGUUACACUUCCAGAUCCCCCGAGAAGGCACCAUAAGGCUGAUGUCUGCUUCCAUCCAUAGUCGUGUUGCCAUCGCUGUAGCUUCAAGACUUCUGAGGCCUAUUUUUAGCUCCCCCCCUUUUCUAGUUGCACAAAUGCAGGCAAGCUCUCUACCUGUCUGGCUCUGAUUCCCCCAUUCGGUGCUCCCUGUGACUGGAGGGUUUUCCCUACCGAAUUGCAGUAAUGAAUGAAUGAUGAUAGGAAGUGCUUGGUCUUGUGGAGCAUUUAGGGUAGUUACCAGGUGUGGUGCAAAGUCUUGACAUACUGUUUUCCCUGGUAGGAGGUAUAGAUACUGUUAGCCCCAUUCACUUGAUGAGGAGACUGAGUCAACGUGGUUAAGUCGCUUAUCCAAGGCGUGUCACACAGCUGGGAAGGAGCAGGGAUGUGAACCAAGAUGGCCUGGCUUCAGAUGCCAGACCACGGGUGCUCAGUCCCUGCAGAUUCUGAUUCUGUGUGGUGUUGGGCGGGCGCUGGGCAUCUGUACAGGCAGCAGCACAGGUUCUCUCCCUGAUUCUUGGCCAUUUUAUUCUAUUUUAUUUUUUGGGACGGAGUCUAGCUCUGUAGCCAGGCUGGAGUGCAGUGGCGCCAUCUCGGCUCACUGCAAUCUCCGCCUCCCGGGUUCAGGUGAUUCUCCUGCCUCAGCCUCCCGAGUAGCUGGGAUUACAGGCGCGCACCACCACACCCAGCUAAUUUUUGUGUUUUUAGUACAGACGGGGUUUCACCAUGUUGGCCAGGAUGGUCUCCAUCUCCUGACCUCGUGAUCUGCCCGCCUCGGCCUCCCAAAGUGCUGGGAUUACAGGCGUGAGCCACCGCACCCGGCUGCUACAUCUCUUUUUUUAAGAUAAAGGAGCCCAUGGAGGGUUGCAGCAUUCCAACUCAUGAGAUCUAGUUACAGAGGGACUGGAAAAGCCUGCCAUUGCUCCGCCCGUCUUUGUGUUUCAGAAGGAUAAAGGACAAAAGUCCCCUGCAGAGCAAAAAAACUUGUCGGAUUCGGGAGAGGAGCCUCGGGGGGAGGCUGAGGCCCCCCACCAUGGCACGGGUCACCCCGAGUCAGCUGGCGAGCAUGCCCUAGAACCUCCUGCCCCUGCUGGCGCCUCAGCCAGCACUCCUCCGCCUCCCGCUCCUGAAGCCCAGCUUCCUCCUUUUCCGCGAGAACUGGCAGGGAGGUCAGCUGGCGGCUCCAGUCCUGAAGGCGGAGAAGAUUCUGACAGAGAAGAUGGAAAUUACUGCCCUCCUGUCAAGCGAGAAAGAACAUCCUCUUUAACCCAGUUCCCACCCUCACAGUCAGAGGAAAGGAGCAGUGGCUUCCGGUUGAAGCCACCAACGCUGAUCCACGGCCAAGCCCCCAGCGCAGGUCUGCCAAGCCAGAAGCCCAAGGAGCAGCAGCGGAGCGUGCUUCGCCCGGCAGUGUUACAAGCUCCGCAGCCAAAGGCGCUGUCCCAGACUGUCCCCAGCAGUGGCACCAACGGGGUCAGCCUCCCAGCAGACUGCACGGGGGCAGUGCCCGCAGCAUCCCCUGACACUGCUGCAUGGAGAAGUCCUUCCGAAGCUGCCGAUGAGGUGUGUGCACUUGAGGAGAAAGAGCCCCAGAAAAAUGAGUCCAGCAAUGCCUCUGAAGAGGAAGCCUGUGAGAAAAAAGACCCCGCCACACAGCAAGCCUUUGUAUUUGGGCAGAACUUGAGGGACAGAGUUAAGCUGAUAAAUGAGAGCGUGGACGAAGCCGACAUGGAGAAUGCUGGACACCCCAGCGCAGACACGCCAACCGCAACGAACUAUUUCCUCCAGUAUAUCAGUUCCAGUUUAGAGAACUCAACCAAUAGUGCCGACGCCUCCAGCAACAAAUUUGUAUUUGGCCAGAACAUGAGCGAGCGAGUUUUGAGCCCCCCAAAAUUAAACGAGGUCAGUUCAGAUGCCAACAGGGAAAAUGCAGCUGCCGAGUCAGGGUCUGAGUCCUCGUCCCAGGAGGCCACCCCUGAGAAAGAGUCCCUGGCUGAGUCGGCAGCCGCCUACACCAAGGCAACAGCGCGGAAGUGUUUGUUGGAAAAAGUGGAAGUCAUCACCGGGGAGGAGGCGGAGAGCAAUGUGUUACAGAUGCAGUGCAAGCUGUUUGUCUUUGACAAGACCUCACAGUCCUGGGUGGAGAGAGGCCGGGGGCUGCUCAGACUCAAUGACAUGGCGUCCACCGAUGACGGCACACUACAGUCCCGACUAGUGAUGCGGACCCAGGGGAGCCUGCGACUGAUCCUCAACACCAAGCUGUGGGCCCAGAUGCAGAUCGACAAGGCCAGCGAGAAGAGCAUUCGCAUCACAGCCAUGGACACCGAGGACCAGGGCGUGAAGGUCUUCCUGAUCUCGGCCAGCUCCAAGGACACAGGUCAGUUGUAUGCAGCCCUGCACCACCGCAUCCUGGCCCUGCGCAGCCGCGUGGAGCAGGAGCAGGAGGCCAAGAUGCCCGCGCCUGAGCCUGGGGCAGCCCCAUCCAACGAGGAGGACGACAGCGACGAUGACGAUGUCCUGGCUCCUUCAGGGGCCACCGCAGCUGGUGCUGGUGACGAAGGGGACGGGCAGACGACCGGGAGCACAUAGCGGCCGGGAGCCCGGCUGCACACCAGGCUGCUGCUUUGUCCGUCUAUCCACCCGCCCACCCGCCCCCACCCCACCGGCAGCGUCCAGGUGCGGGGCCGGGAACCACACACCCCACUGGGCCGGCCACAGUCUGGACCCGCACGUCCUGUUCAAAAGCAGACUCGGGAACUGCCUGAAUGUGGUUUGGGACACGAGACCUCAUCAUAUUGAUGAGCGAACAAACAAGAACAUUUCCUCCCUCCCCUCCUUUGAAUUGAAAUGGCACAUUAAGACUUGUCACGGCUUCUCACUGGGACUGGAGACCUCGUUCCUUCACCCCGCGUGUCGCCAGCCUCUGGGUCCAGCCAGAGCCCCUGGCUUCUCCGCCACCCACACCCUUCCCACCCUGCUGUGGGGCCCUGCCUUUGUGGGGAGCAGCCAGCCCUCUGCCCCUGCCCAGGGCUCCCCAACUAUAGGCCUGGGACCCCCGCCCAGCUUGGGGGGCUGCUCGUACGAGUGUAGACACUGGGCCCAUUGGACGUGCUGUUAACUACUAUCUUCAUUUCCCACUUCCCCUCUCUGAUUGGGGGUGUAUAUUUUACAUCUUUUUUUCUUUUUAUUUUCGAAGGCUUUGUUUUGGUUUCUUAGGUUAAGAUGCUCUCGAGCGUUGAGCAGGCACAGCUCUGUCGAGGUCCCUGUCCCCCACCUGUGGUUCUGGCCUCUGAGGUUGGGGGACUACUUGUUUCCCACCCCAGGUUCCUCCAGGCCAAGUCAUGGGGUGAUGAGGAGUUGGGGCCCUGUCUGUCCUAGGCCUGGAGAGUGCCUGUCUGGGAAAAGGUCACUGGACCUGGAAGGGUCCCCAGGGUCCCCUGACUCCCGUCUCCAUCUGUCACGUGGUUCACCAUCAUCAGGCACCAGGCGCAAACUGCUUCCCGCUGUUGGCCAUCCCUUCCCCAGCCACAGGUGUCCCUGCCCCCAGGACAGUCCAGGGCCAGGGGCUUCUGUGAGAGGCAGAGGGGGACCCUCACCAAAUCUUGGUGGAAGAGCCCAGGGGCUGGUCCCAGAACAGGCAGUCUCACAAGCACGCAGCACACUGGAGUGGACGCCUGUGCCCACCCGAGCCUGGAGCAUGGCCAAGAGCCAGCUUGCACCACCCACCUGGGAGGCCGAGGAGGAGGUCCCCUGGGCACAGGGCCUCUUUGGGACUUCAGAGGAAAUCUCCCAGUCCCACUCUCGGAGGGUUAAGAGAAGGCCUCCUGCAGCUGUGCCGUCCACACCUCUAGGUCGCCAGAGCCCUGGCCCCCAGCCCCCAGCAAGCCUGAGCCCGGGAAGAACCAGAGGCCCUCCCGAGAGACCCAGUCACACGUCUCUGCUUUAAGCCUUAGCCAGCUAGUGACGAGUACAACGAGAUAACGCCCAUGUGUUUUGGAACAUUUAUGUAAGAUUGUCAUAUGAAAUGUAUUUGGGAACUACAUUAAACUUUUAACUAAAA